CUCUUUCUCCUCCACGUGGGGACGCAGGAUGGCGGCAGCAGUGCCGGACGAGGCGGUGGCGCGCGAUGUGCAGCGGUUGCUAGUGCAGUUCCAGGAUGAGGGCGGGCAGCUGCUGGGUUCCCCGUUCGACGUGCCCGUGGACAUCACCCCGGACAGGCUGCAGCUCGUGUGCAACGCGCUACUGGCCCAGGAGGAUCCCCUGCCACUGGCUUUCUUUGUCCACGAUGCUGAGAUCGUCUCCUCACUGGGGAAGACGUUGGAGUCCCAGGCAGUGGAGACAGAGAAGGUCCUAGACAUCAUCUACCAGCCACAGGCUAUCUUCAGAGUCCGGGCUGUGACUCGCUGCACCAGCUCCUUGGAGGGUCACAGUGAGGCAGUCAUUUCUGUGGCCUUCAGCCCUACGGGAAAGUACCUGGCCAGUGGCUCUGGAGACACCACCGUGCGCUUCUGGGAUCUCAGCACAGAGACACCACAUUUCACAUGCAAGGGACACAGACACUGGGUCCUUAGUAUAUCCUGGUCUCCAGAUGGCAGGAAGCUGGCCUCAGGCUGCAAGAAUGGCCAGAUUCUCCUCUGGGACCCAAGCACAGGGAAGCAGGUGGGCAGGACCCUCGCUGGCCACAGCAAGUGGAUCACAGGCCUGAGCUGGGAGCCCCUCCAUGCGAACCCUGAGUGCCGCUAUGUGGCCAGCAGCUCCAAGGAUGGCAGUGUGCGGAUCUGGGACACAACUGCAGGCCGCUGUGAGCGCAUCCUCACCGGGCACACCCAGUCGGUCACCUGUCUCCGGUGGGGAGGGGACGGGCUUCUCUACUCUGCCUCCCAGGACCGCACCAUCAAAGUCUGGAGAGCUCAUGACGGUGUGCUGUGCCGGACUCUGCAAGGCCACGGCCACUGGGUGAACACCAUGGCCCUCAGCACUGACUAUGCCCUGCGCACUGGGGCCUUUGAACCUGCUGAGGCCUCAGUUAAUCCCCAAGACCUCCAAGGAUCCUUGCAGGAGUUGAAGGAGAGGGCUCUGAGCCGAUACAACCUCGUGCGGGGCCAGGGUCCAGAGAGGCUGGUGUCUGGCUCCGACGACUUCACCUUAUUCCUGUGGUCCCCAGCAGAGGACAAAAAGCCUCUCACUCGGAUGACAGGACACCAAGCUCUCAUCAACCAGGUGCUCUUCUCUCCUGACUCCCGCAUCGUGGCUAGUGCCUCCUUUGACAAGUCCAUCAAGCUGUGGGAUGGCAGGACGGGCAAGUACCUGGCUUCCCUACGCGGCCACGUGGCUGCCGUGUACCAGAUUGCGUGGUCAGCUGACAGUCGGCUCCUGGUCAGCGGCAGCAGUGACAGCACACUGAAGGUGUGGGAUGUGAAGGCCCAGAAGCUGGCCAUGGACCUGCCCGGCCACGCGGAUGAGGUAUAUGCUGUUGACUGGAGUCCAGAUGGCCAGAGAGUGGCAAGUGGUGGGAAGGACAAAUGCCUCCGGAUAUGGAGGAGAUGAGACGGCCCGAAGUUCUCUCUGACCCCCACCUCGACUCGGCCUCUGCCAGCUGCCUUCCCUGCCAGAGAACAAAGGCUGAGAUGGCAGUGCACACACCCUCCCCACCAGUGGGGACCUGAGAAUGCGUGUGGCCUGCUGUCCUCGAUAGACCGGAAUGGGGUUUUCCCACAGAUCCCCGCCUGUGGCACACCCCAGAGCCAGAAAUCGAAGGUCACAGGAAGUUGUCACUGAACUUGGCCCGUGUCUGCUACUCUGUACCUUGCUGGUACAGACAGGGGUGGUGGGCAGCCAGGCUCUAUGAGUGGGCCCCUAGUGUCAGCUCUGUACAGGGUCAGAUCCCAGGUUCUAUGACCAAAUAAGUAACUUAAGUUUUGUGUGUUGGGUUCUAAUUCCUUGUCCUAGAAUCCCCAUGACUCAAUCAAGGACUGUGCUAAAUGAGAUUGUCCAGCCCCCGCCCUUGCACUGGACUACGCCAAAACCACACUGACCAGGCACUUGCCUUCCCUCUCUUCCCCCGUGUUGGUAAGAGAGAGGCCAGUUGUGAUAGUGGCCAAGGAGAAUCUAGGGCUGUAUUGUUGUCCACUGCAGUAGGCACCGGCCACAUGUGACUGCUGGCAUGAAAUAGAAGUGCAGUUCCUCCAUCGCACUGGGUAAGGCCUCCAGUAUUGGACAGCACACAGAAAGGUUUUCAUCAUCAAGAGAGUUCUGCUGGUCAGCCCUGCUCCAGGGGAUGCCUCUGCCUUCGCAUAGCACACUGCUUGAGGCCCUGCCAGGCACCAAGCACUGCCCUGGGCCCAUGGGAUAGAGCGGGGAAGGUGAUGGCUCUUCCAGAGGAUUCCCUCAGAUGGGGAGGCAGCAGUAUGAGCUCUGAGCAGAAGUGGGUAUUGUUGAUACAGAGGAAGUUCUUUGCCACGAGAACUUUCAAGCAGUGAAAGGAAUUCCCAUCAGGACUCAGACCCCAGGCCGAGAUCUUGCCCUGAAUGUACCCUGCCUCUGCUUUCUCCUGCAUCCCAUGCUAAGCAGGGUCAUGGUCUGAACUACUCAGAUUGGAUUUCCAAACCAUCCUUGUAUAAACUGCUCAGAACUAGCAUCUUGCUCCUUCUUACCCUCCUCCACCCUUGUCUGUGCUUUUGGGUUUUGCGCGUCACCUAGCUGUGGUGCUUGGCCUCCACCUUGCACAUAUCUGCAGUGAGGCUACAUAAGAAGCGAACAAAACUAUCAGCCACUGAGCUCCUUGGUGCCAGCUGUUUGUCUGCUGUGCUCUCAGACUGCACCAGGCCUGGAAGGUUCUCAAGCUCCAAAACUUUUGAUGAGGAAACAACAUAAGAAAUGAUUAGCCCAUGCCCUCACAUCUAGUAAGAGAAAGCUGGGAUUAAACCAGGCCCUGCCCCAAAGCUUAUUGUGCACUUUGUACCACAUCCCUCCGUCCAGAGCUCAAGCUAGUUUGACAGUUCAUGGGCCACCACGUCUGUCCAUGACAGCUAUUUCUGUAUUUUUCUGGUGUAAGAGCCUUUUAGUCUUAGAGCACCAGUCUCCCUGUUCCCCUACCCCGCCCCACUGGGGAAGGGGUGAUGGCAGCAUCCUAUUGCCUAGCUGCCUGUUUUCUAUCUCCCCACCCAUGUAGACUCUGUCCUGGUGGAAGCUAGGAGGUGGGUGCCAGCCAGCCCAUCUGAGGCUGUCUGCAGCAUAAAGCAGACUUUAGGGUGCUGGAUGACCUGCAGUUCUUUAAUGAGGGACCUAGACCCAGCCCAGAUUUGGAGGAGGAGGGAGUCUAGCAGCUGUGGGCAGUGGCUGAGCCUGGCAUGGCCUGGCCUGAGAUGCCUCCAGGUGAAUGGGGCCCCUAUGUAGCCUUGGCCCCAGCCCAGGGGUGGGGUGCCCAUACCACUCUGCCAGACCCCGGGCCCGCAGGGUGCUGGUGGUAUGGUAGGUCUCAUGGCUCUGGUUUCUGAGGGCCUGGGGUUGAAGCUGAAAGUAGGUGAGGGGUGUCCUGGGGCCCUCCCCCUUAACAGGGAAAUAGGUAUUCCAGAUCCUCCAGCCUCCGCAUCUCCUCCGGCCCGAUGGACACGAUCUUUUGCCGGGGUUCCUUGCGCCGCACGGUGAUCUGGAUGGGGUAGUUCUCAGGAAAGCUGCUGAAGUCAGUGGCCAGGGUUGCAAACUGAAGUGAAACAAGAAAACCCUUCAGAGUUCCUUCCCAGAUCUGAACCUGGCUCUCUCUCUGUCUCUAUCACCCCUUUUUUUUCUGUCUGCUGACUCAGACCUUAAACAGCCUUAUCCAACCUAGCCAUUGACGCAGGAAACAGGUGCAAAGAUGCAUGACUCAAGCCUGUACCUCCUCAUUAUGGGAUAUUUCCAACCAAAGGGCUGUCUGUACUCAGGCCUCUAUACCCCCAUACCCCUACCCCAUACCCAGGCUGUUCCCUUCUUCGUCCCCCUUUAGCCUCUUGUCUUCCCUAUUUCUUUCAAUGCCCUUGACUUCCCAGCCUACUCACAAUCAUGGGCACUGAAUUGCAGAGUCUAAAAACCAAUGGCUUUGGAAGGGGAACAUUAUAGUGAUGUUGAAAAAUACAUUCGUUUGCAUUCCUAGUGGGCCCCAGAGUGGCUUAAUCCUUAAACCUCCCAGAAGCAUGCAUUCUGGAAUUGAUGCUUCUUGACCCAGGCAGAAGGAAAGCUAGCCAGAUGAGUCAUGUGGGCAUAGGGGUGUUCCCAACCUCCAAAGCCCUGGUUCCCUGGCUUUGGACUUCUCUCCACCCCCAAGGCCCCUCUUUUCCCAGGGCUCACUUUGUAGGGCUUGCACCACUUCCCCACCCCAGCUGUGUUGGCUGCACGGACACUGAGGCAGUAACACGUGUUAGGCUUUAGCUCCAUCAGCUUGACAGUAGUGCCCAAAAUCUUGUUGAAGAUCCAUGGACGAUUCUUUGCCUCGGGCAACUCAUUCUCCUGUGUCUUGGCCACCUCCUGUAACAGGAGCUGGUAGAAACUGACCGGCUGCUUGCCCAAGGCGUAGGUCCAGGAAAUCUAGGGGAAGAGAGAGCCCCGAGGCUUCCUCAGAUAUGUCCUGUCCUUCCUGUCCCUUCACCCUCCCAACUGGGGUCAGGACGUCCCAUGCCCAUCCCCUGCUCCUGCUGGGGCCCAGGCAGGUCAGAUGGAAGGUGCAAGGUACUGCAGCACUGAGUGUGGAACCCCUGCCCCGAAGCAUGUACUACUCUCCUGGGCAGCCCCACCCACUUUAGGGUACACCCUCAUUCCAUAUUUCUUAUACGCCAGGGGUCCUCAACCCUUGGGCCACCAACUGAUAGCAGUCCAUGGCCUGUUAGGAACUGGAUAGCACAGCAGGAGGAGAUUGGUGGGCGAGCAAGCGAAGCUUCAUCUGUAUUUACAGCUGCUCCCCACGGCUCAGGGUACCACCUGAGCUCUGCCUCCUGUCAGAUCAGCAGAGGCAUUAGAUUCCCAUAGGCACGUGAACCCUAUUGUGAAUUGUAUGGGAGGGAUCUAAGUUGAAUGCUCCUUAUGAGAAUCUAAUGCCUGAUGAUCUGUCAUUGUCUCCCAUCACCCCCAAAUGGGACCCUCUCGUUGCAGGAAAACAAGCUCAGGGCUCCCACAGUUUCUACAUUAUGGUGAGUUGUAUAAUUAUUUCAUUAUAUAUUACAAUGUAAUAAUAAUAGAAAUAAAGUACACAAUAAAUGUAAUAUGCUUGACUCAUCCUGAAA